ACAAAGCGCGCAUGCGCGCGGAUCACCGCAGGCUCCUGUGCCUUGGGCUUGAGCUUUGUGGCAGUUAAUGGCUUUUCUGCACGUAUCUCUGGUGUUUACUUGAGAAGCCUGGCUGUGUCCUUGCUGUAGGAGCCGGAGUAGCUCAGAGUGAUCUUGUCUGAGGAAAGGCCAGCCCCACUUGGGGUUAAUAAACCGCGAUGGGUGAACCCUCAGGAGGCUAUACUUACACCCAAACGUCGAUAUUCCUUUUCCACGCUAAGAUUCCUUUUGGUUCCAAGUCCAAUAUGGCAACUCUAAAGGAUCAGCUGAUUUAUAAUCUUCUAAAGGAAGAACAGACCCCCCAGAAUAAGAUUACAGUUGUUGGGGUUGGUGCUGUUGGCAUGGCCUGUGCCAUCAGUAUCUUAAUGAAGGACUUGGCAGAUGAACUUGCUCUUGUUGAUGUCAUCGAAGACAAAUUGAAGGGAGAGAUGAUGGAUCUCCAACAUGGCAGCCUUUUCCUUAGAACACCAAAGAUUGUCUCUGGCAAAGACUAUAAUGUAACUGCAAACUCCAAGCUGGUCAUUAUCACGGCUGGGGCACGUCAGCAAGAGGGAGAAAGCCGUCUUAAUUUGGUCCAGCGUAACGUGAACAUCUUUAAAUUCAUCAUUCCUAAUGUUGUAAAAUACAGCCCGAACUGCAAGUUGCUUAUUGUUUCAAAUCCAGUGGAUAUCUUGACCUACGUGGCUUGGAAGAUAAGUGGUUUUCCCAAAAACCGUGUUAUUGGAAGCGGUUGCAAUCUGGAUUCAGCCCGAUUCCGUUACCUAAUGGGGGAAAGGCUGGGAGUUCACCCAUUAAGCUGUCAUGGGUGGGUCCUUGGGGAACAUGGAGAUUCCAGUGUGCCUGUAUGGAGUGGAAUGAAUGUUGCUGGUGUCUCUCUGAAGACUCUGCACCCAGAUUUAGGGACUGAUAAAGAUAAGGAACAGUGGAAAGAGGUUCACAAGCAGGUGGUUGAGAGUGCUUAUGAGGUGAUCAAACUCAAAGGCUACACAUCCUGGGCUAUUGGACUCUCUGUAGCAGAUUUGGCAGAGAGUAUAAUGAAGAAUCUUAGGCGGGUGCACCCAGUUUCCACCAUGAUUAAGGGUCUUUACGGAAUAAAGGAUGAUGUCUUCCUUAGUGUUCCUUGCAUUUUGGGACAGAAUGGAAUCUCAGACCUUGUGAAGGUGACUCUGACUUCUGAGGAAGAGGCCCGUUUGAAGAAGAGUGCAGAUACACUUUGGGGGAUCCAAAAGGAGCUGCAAUUUUAAAGUCUUCUGAUGUCAUAUCAUUUCACUGUCUAGGCUACAACAGGAUUCUAGGUGGAGGUUGUGCAUGUUGUCCUUUUUAUCUGAUCUGUGAUUAAAGCAGUAAUAUUUUAAGAUGGACUGGGAAAAACAUCAACUCCUGAAGUUAGAAAUAAGAAUGGUUUGUAAAAUCCACAGCUAUAUCCUGAUGCUGGAUGGUAUUAAUCUUGUGUAGUCUUCAACUGGUUAGUGUGAAAUAGUUCUGCCACCUCUGACGCACCACUGCCAAUGCUGUACGUACUGCAUUUGCCCCUUGAGCCAGGUGGAUGUUUACCGUGUGUUAUAUAACUUCCUGGCUCCUUCACUGAACAUGCCUAGUCCAACAUUUUUUCCCAGUGAGUCACAUCCUGGGAUCCAGUGUAUAAAUCCAAUAUCAUGUCUUGUGCAUAAUUCUUCCAAAGGAUCUUAUUUUGUGAACUAUAUCAGUAGUGUACAUUACCAUAUAAUGUAAAAAGAUCUACAUACAAACAAUGCAACCAACUAUCCAAGUGUUAUACCAACUAAAACCCCCAAUAAACCUUGAACAGUGACUACUUUGGUUAAUUCAUUAUAUUAAGAUAUAAAGUCAUAAAGCUGCUAGUUAUUAUAUUAAUUUGGAAAUAUUAGGCUAUUCUUGGGCAACCCUGCAACGAUUUUUUCUAACAGGGAUAUUAUUGACUAAUAGCAGAGGAUGUAAUAGUCAACUGAGUUGUAUUGGUACCACUUCCAUUGUAAGUCCCAAAGUAUUAUAUAUUUGAUAAUAAUGCUAAUCAUAAUUGGAAAGUAACAUUCUAUAUGUAAAUGUAAAAUUUAUUUGCCAACUGAAUAUAGGCAAUGAUAGUGUGUCACUAUAGGGAACACAGAUUUUUGAGAUCUUGUCCUCUGGAAGCUGGUAACAAUUAAAAACAAUCUUAAGGCAGGGUGCAGUGGCUCAUGCCUAUAAUCCCAGCACUUUGGGAAGCCCAGGUGGGCUGAUCACUGGAGGCCAGGAAUUGGGGACCAGCCUGGCCAACACAACAAAACCCCAUCUGUUAAAAAAACAAAACAAAACCAAAAAAAACAAGUAACCUUGGUGGAUGUCUACUCAAGUUUUCUGCACAUUUUUCUGAAAAUACAACUGUGACCCUUA